AGAAGGGUUCGCUGAGAGAGAGCUGACUCCUUUAGAGGGUUAGGGACAGGCAGGGGGAGGUGCCAGGAACAUUCCUACCAUGGAGGGGGAGAAGAUGUGCCCAAGGAAAUCUACUUUGAAACCUGAUGCCACAGUUGGGGCUUGUACUGACCUCUGCCCUCAGCCUGUCUUUUAGCCCAGUUUCUUUCCUGUUGAUUUAUGGAGCUAGCUAUGACUCCAUCCUCCAUCAACACCAAAGUGCUUGCCAUUCCCAGAACAGCCAAGCUCUUCCCCCUCCCUGUCUUUGUACCUGCUGAAUUUAGUCUGGAAUGCCUCCCUCCCUUCUCUCUCUGCCUUAUCCUCUAAGACAUAGUUCAAAUAUUACCUCUUUUUUUUUUUUUUUUUUUUGAGACGGAGUCUCAUUCUAUCGCCCAGGCUGGAGAGCAGUGGCAUGAUCUUGCCUACUGCAACCUCUGCCUCCUGGGUUCAAGUGACUCCCCUGCCUCAGCCUCCCAAGUACCUGGGACUGUUUACAGGCACAUGCCACCAUACCCAGCUAAUGUUUGUAUUUUUAGUAGAGACAGGGUUUCACCAUGUUGGUCAGGCUGGUCUCAAACUCCUGACCUCAAGUGAUCCACCUGCCUCAGCCUCCCAAAGUGUUGGGAUUACAAGCGUGAGCCACUGCAACUCGCCGAAAUGUCACCUCUUCUAUGAAGCCUUCUCUGACCUCAGUAGCCUGCUAAGUUACUGUGCCCUUGUAGUCUUUUGACCUCUUAUUACAGCAUUGAUCUCACUGAUGAUUUAGUUUCCCCUACCUUCUUUUUUUGGUGAGGCUGUUUUACUUUUUGGAUUAUAAUGAAGUAGGUUUUUAAAAAAUAAUGACAUAGAAGGGCAGGGAAAUGAGCAGAGAGCCCCAUUGAAUCUCAGGACAAAGUUCAUAUAUGCCCAUGACGAGGGUUGUAUCUUCACCUGUUGGAGGUACAUACAUAAAAUGCAGGGCUAUUUUGUUUUGUUUUUGCUUUUGGAGGCACUGAGAAGUACAAAAGCAGGCCAUGUCUUCGUAAGUUUUUAUUUCUAGUACUUUGUACUUCACCUGCCGUAUACUAGACACUCAAUACAUUUUGUUUCUUUGUUUUUUGAGACAGAGUCUAGCUCUGUUGCCCAGGCUGGAGUGCAGUAGUGUAAACACAGCUCACCGCAGCCUUAACCUCCUGGGCUGAAGCAAUUCUCUUGCCUCAGCCUCCAAAGUAGCUGGGAUUACAGGCACGCACCACUAUGCCUGGCUAACUUUUUAAUUUUUUUGUAGAGACGGGGUCUCACUAUGUUUCCCAGGCCGGUCUGGAACUCCUGAGCUCAAGCAGUCUUUCCACCUUGGCCUCCCAAAGUUCUAGGAUUACCGGUUGAGCCACCGUGGCUGGCCAGUGAAUGUUUGUUGAGUGAUGCAAUACUUAAACAAAUGACCAUACAGUGUGUUAAGGUUCUUAGAGAUGGUAUAGAAUAAAAUUAUUAAGACUUUUGCUGAGUGAGGAGGAUCACUUGAGCCCAGGAGUUUGAGACCAGCCUGGACAACAUAGUGAGACCUUGUCUCUACUAAAAGUAAAAAUAAAAAAAGAAUAGCCAUGUGGUGGCAUGCACCUAUAAUUCUAGCUACUUGGGAAGCUGAGGCAGGAGGAUUGCUUGAGAGUGAGCUAUGAUUGCACCACUGUAUUCCAGCCUGGGCAACAGAGCAAGACCCUGUCUCAAAAAAAAAAUUGGAAAAAAAUUUAAACUUUUAGAUAGCAUUCAUUCAAGAAAUAUUUAUUUAGCCACUCACAUAAUAGCAAGCAGUAAGCUCUAAGAUAUAGUGUUAAGUGUUUGGUGAUUUUGCUGGACUUUGAGAUUAAUAUCAAGAAGGUUGAACAUAAUCUUCCCCAAAUUGCCCUUCCUUUUUCCCUAUCAGAGUCAGAACCUCGGGCUGGAGGGACCUUGGGACUAUCCCAAGUGCAAUUCUGAUGUUCUUAUUGGCUUCAGGGUGCUUGACUUCAAGAUCAAGCGAGGCCUGGAAGGGCCUGGGCCAGGGCUUUCCUUCAGCUCUUGGGCCCCCAAACACGUGUUCCAGCCUUGAGAUGUGGGUGACCGAGCUCUCUGCUCUGUUGACCCAGUCUCAGAAGCAAAAUGAAGAUUAUGAAAAGAUGAUAAAGGCUCUGAGAGAGACAGUGGAGAUCCUGGAGACAAAUCACACAGAAUUAAUGGAACAUGAAGCAUCUCUUAGUAGGAAUGCGCAAGAGGAGAAGUUGUCUUUACAGCAGGUGAUCAAGGAUAUAACCCAGGUCAUGGUGGAAGAAGGGGACAAUAUAGCCCAAGGCUCUGGUCAUGAGAACUCUUUGGAAUUGGACUCUAGUAUCUUCUCCCAGUUUGAUUACCAGGAUGCAGACAAGGCUCUUACUCUGGUGCGUUCAGUGCUGACUCGGAGACGCCAGGCUGUGCAGGACCUAAGGCAGCAGCUUGCAGGCUGUCAAGAGGCUGUGAACUUGUUGCAACAGCAGCAUGAUCAGUGGGAGGAAGAGGGCAAAGCCUUGAGACAGCGGCUGCAGAAGCUCACUGGGGAGCGGGACACUCUGGCAGGGCAGACUGUGGACCUCCAGGGAGAGGUGGACUCUCUCAGCAAGGAGCGAGAGCUGCUGCAGAAGGCCAGGGAAGAGCUGCGGCAGCAGCUGGAGGUGCUAGAGCAGGAGGCAUGGCGCCUGCGAAGGGUAAAUGUGGAGCUUCAGCUGCAGGGGGACUCUGCCCAGGGCCAGAAGGAGGAACAGCAGGAGGAGCUGCACCUGGCUGUCCGGGAGAGGGAGCGUCUUCAGGAGAUGCUGAUGGGCCUGGAAGCCAAACAGUCAGAAUCACUCAGUGAACUGAUCACUCUUCGGGAAGCCCUGGAGUCAAGUCACCUGGAAGGGGAGUUACUGAGGCAAGAGCAAACGGAAGUGACCGCAGCGCUGGCUAGGGCAGAGCAGUCAAUUGCAGAGCUGUCGAGUUCUGAAAACACCCUGAAGACAGAAGUAGCUGAUCUUCGGGCUGCAGCUGUCAAGCUCAGUGCCUUAAAUGAGGCUUUGGCGUUAGAUAAAGUUGGGCUGAACCAGCAGCUUCUCCAGUUAGAGGAGGAGAACCAGUCUGUGUGCAGCAGAAUGGAGGCCGCAGAGCAGGCGAGAAAUGCUUUGCAGGUCGACCUGGCGGAGGCAGAGAAGAGGAGGGAAGCCCUGUGGGAAAAGAACACUCACCUGGAGGCUCAGCUGCAGAAAGCUGAGGAGGCUGGGGCUGAGCUGCAGGCAGAUCUCAGGGACAUCCAAGAAGAGAAGGAAGAAAUUCAAAAGAAACUAAGUGAGUCACGUCACCAGCAGGAGGCAGCCACGACUCAGCUGGAGCAGCUACAUCAGGAGGCAAAGCGACAGGAAGAAGUGCUUGCCAGGGCAGUCCAGGAGAAGGAGGCCCUAGUACGAGAGAAAGCGGCUCUAGAGGUGCGGCUGCAGGCCGUGGAGCGUGACCGGCAGGACCUCGCUGAACAACUACAGGGGCUCAGCUCAGCCAAGGAGCUACUGGAGAGCAGUCUGUUUGAAGCCCAACAACAAAAUUCUGUGAUAGAGGUCACCAAGGGGCAGCUGGAGGUCCAGAUUCAAACUGUCACUCAAGCCAAGGAAGUAAUCCAAGGGGAAGUGAGGUGCCUGAAGCUGGAACUGGACACUGAACGGAGUCAGGCAGAGCAGGAGCGGGAUGCUGCAGCCAGACAGCUGGCCCAGGCUGAGCAAGAAGGGAAGACUGCCUUGGAGCAGCAGAAGGCAGCCCAUGAGAAAGAGGUGAACCAGCUCCGGGAGAAAUGGGAGAAGGAGCGCUCCUGGCACCAGCAGGAGCUGGCAAAGGCUCUGGAGAGCUUAGAAAGGGAAAAAAUGGAGCUGGAAAUGAGGCUAAAGGAGCAGCAGACAGAAAUGGAGGCCAUCCAGGCCCAGAGGGAAGAAGAACGGACCCAGGCAGAGAGUGCCCUAUGCCAGAUGCAGCUGGAAACAGAGAAGGAGAGAGUAUCCCUCCUGGAGACACUGCUGCAGACGCAGAAGGAGCUAGCAGAUGCCAGCCAACAACUGGAACGACUGAGGCAGGACAUGAAAGUCCAGAAAUUAAAGGAGCAGGAGACCACUGGGAUACUACAGACCCAGCUCCAGGAGGCUCAACGGGAGCUGAAGGAGGCAGCCCGGCAGCACAGAGAUGACCUUGCUGCCCUCCAAGAAGAGAGCAGCUCCCUGCUGCAGGAUAAGAUGGACCUGCAGAAGCAGGUGGAGGACUUGAAGUCUCAGCUGGUGGCCCAGGAUGACUCCCAGAGGCUGGUGGAGCAGGAGGUUCAGGAGAAGCUGAGAGAGACCCAGGAGUAUAACCGAAUUCAGAAGGAGCUGGAGAGAGAGAAAGCCAGCCUGACUCUCUCACUGAUGGAAAAGGAACAGAGACUCCUUGUUUUACAAGAAGCUGACUCUAUUCGACAACAAGAGCUGAGUGCCCUGCGCCAGGACAUGCAGGAGGCCCAGGGAGAACAGAAAGAGCUCAGUGCUCAGAUGGAAUUACUAAGGCAAGAGGUGAAGGAAAAGGAGGCUGACUUUCUGGCCCAGGAAGCACAGCUGCUGGAGGAGCUGGAGGCGUCUCAUAUCACGGAGCAGCAGCUGCGAGCCUCCUUGUGGGCCCAGGAAGCCAAGGCAGCCCAACUACAGCUGCGACUGCGCAGCACAGAGAGCCAGCUAGAAGCGCUGGCCGCAGAGCAGCAGCCCGGGAACCAGGCCCAGGCCCAGGCCCAGCUGGCCAGCCUCUACUCUGCCCUGCAGCAGGCCCUGGGGUCUGUUUGUGAGAGCAGGCCUGAGCUGAGUGGUGGGGGAGACUCUGCUCCUUCCGUCUGGGGCCUUGAGCCAGACCAGAAUGGAGCUAGGAGCCUCUUUAAGAGAGGGCCCCUGCUGACUGCUCUCUCCGCUGAGGCAGUAGCAUCUGCCCUCCACAAGCUUCAUCAAGACCUGUGGAAGACUCAACAGACCCGGGAUGUUCUGAGGGAUCAGGUCCAGAAACUGGAAGAGCGUCUAACUGAUACUGAGGCUGAGAAGAGCCAGGUCCACACAGAGUUGCAGGAUCUGCAGAGACAGCUCUCCCAGAAUCAGGAAGAGAAAUCUAAGUGGGAAGGAAAGCAGAACUCCCUAGAAUCUGAGCUGAUGGAACUACAUGAAACUAUGGCAUCCUUACAGAGUCGCCUGCGGAGAGCAGAGCUACAGCGAAUGGAAGCCCAGGGUGAGCGAGAGUUACUUCAGGCAGCCAAGGAGAACCUGACAGCCCAGGUGGAACACCUGCAAGCAGCUGUCGUAGAAGCCAGGGCUCAGGCAAGUGCUGCUGGCAUCCUGGAAGAAGACCUGAGAACGGCUCGCUCAGCACUGAAGCUGAAAAAUGAGGAAGUAGAGAGUGAGCGUGAGAGAGCCCAGGCUCUGCAAGAGCAGGGCGAACUGAAGGUGGCCCAAGGGAAGGCUCUGCAAGAGAAUUUGGCCCUCCUGACCCAGACCCUAGCUGAAAGAGAAGAGGAGGUGGAGACUCUGCGGGGACAAAUCCAGGAACUGGAGAAGCAACGGGAAAUGCAGAAGGCUGCUUUGGAAUUGCUGUCUCUGGACCUGAAGAAGAGGAACCAAGAGGUAGAUCUGCAGCAAGAACAGAUUCAGGAGCUAGAGAAGUGUAGGUCUGUUUUAGAGCAUCUGCCCAUGGCCGUCCAGGAGCGAGAGCAGAAGCUGACUGUGCAGAGGGAGCAGAUCAGAGAGCUCGAGAAGGAUCGGGAGACUCAGAGGAACGUCUUGGAGCAUCAGCUUCUAGAACUUGAGAAGAAAGACCAAAUGAUUGAGUCCCAGAGAGGACAGGUUCAGGACCUGAAAAAGCAGUUGGUUACUCUGGAAUGCCUGGCCCUGGAACUGGAGGAAAACCAUCACAAGAUGGAGUGCCAGCAAAAACUGAUCAAGGAGCUGGAGGGCCAGAGGGAAACCCAGAGAGUGGCUUUGACCCACCUUACGCUGGACCUAGAAGAAAGGAGCCAGGAGCUGCAGGCACAAAGCAGCCAGAUCCAUGACCUGGAGAGCCACAGCACCGUUCUGGCAAGAGAGCUGCAGGAGAGGGACCAGGAGGUGAAGUCUCAGCGAGAACAGAUCGAGGAGCUGCAGAGGCAGAAAGAGCAUCUGACUCAGGAUCUCGAGAGGAGAGACCAGGAGCUGAUGCUGCAGAAGGAGAGGAUUCAGGUUCUCGAGGAUCAGAGGACCCGGCAGACCAAGAUCCUGGAGGAGGACCUGGAACAGAUCAAGCUGUCCUUGAGAGAGCGAGGCCGGGAGCUGACCACUCAGAGGCAGCUGAUGCAGGAACGGGCAGAGGAAGGGAAGGGCCCAAGUAAAGCACAGCGCGGGAGCCUAGAGCACAUGAAGCUGAUCCUGCGUGAUAAGGAGAAGGAGGUGGAAUGUCAGCAGGAGCAUAUCCAUGAACUCCAGGAGCUCAAAGACCAGCUGGAGCAGCAGCUCCAGGGCCUGCACAGGAAGGUAGGUGAGACCAGCCUCCUCCUGUCCCAGCGAGAGCAGGAAAUAGUGGUCCUGCAGCAGCAACUGCAGGAAGCCAGGGAACAAGGGGAGCUGAAGGAGCAGUCACUUCAGAGUCAACUGGAUGAGGCCCAGAGAGCCCUAGCCCAGAGGGACCAGGAACUGGAGGCUCUGCAGCAAGAACAGCAGCAGGCCCAGGGACAGGAGGAGAGGGUGAAGGAAAAGGCAGACGCCCUCCAGGGAGCUCUGGAGCAAGCCCAUAUGACACUGAAGGAGCGUCAUGGAGAGCUUCAGGACCACAAGGAACAGGCACGAAGGCUGGAGGAAGAGCUGGCAGUGGAGGGACGGCGGGUCCAGGCCCUGGAGGAGGUGCUGGGAGACCUAAGGGCUGAGUCUCGGGAACAGGAGAAAGCUCUGUUGGCCCUCCAGCAGCAGUGUGCUGAGCAGGCACAGGAGCAUGAGGUGGAGACCAGGGCCCUGCAGGACAGCUGGCUGCAGGCCCAGGCAGUGCUCAAGGAACGGGACCAGGAGCUGGAAGCUCUGCGGGCAGAAAGUCAGUCCUCCCGGCAUCAGGAGGAGGCUGCCCGGGCCCGGGCUGAGGCUCUGCAGGAGGCCCUUGGCAAGGCUCAUGCUGCCCUGCAGGGGAAAGAGCAGCAUCUCCUCGAGCAGGCAGAAUUGAGCCGCAGUCUGGAGGCCAGCACUGCAACCCUGCAAGCCUCCCUGGAUGCCUGCCAGGCACACAGUCGGCAGCUGGAGGAGGCUCUGAGGAUACAAGAAGGUGAGAUCCAGGACCAGGAUCUCCGAUACCAGGAGGAUGUGCAGCAGCUGCAGCAGGCACUUGCCCAGAGGGAUGAAGAGCUGAGACAUCAGCAGGAACGGGAGCAGCUGCUGGAGAAGUCUCUGGCCCAGAGGGUCCAAGAGAAUAUGAUCCAAGAGAAGCAGAAUCUGGGGCAAGAGAGAGAAGAGGAGGAGAUAAGGGGCCUUCAUCAGAGUGUAAGGGAGCUACAGCUGACUCUAGCCCAAAAGGAACAGGAGAUUCUGGAGCUGAGGGAGACCCAGCAAAGGAACAACCUGGAAGCCUUACCCCACAGCCACAAAACCUCCCCAAUGGAGGAACAAUCUCUAAAACUUGAUUCUUUAGAGCCCAGGCUGCAGCGGGAGCUGGAGCGGCUACAGGCAGCCCUGAGACAGACAGAAGCCAGGGAGAUUGAGUGGAGGGAGAAGGCCCAGGACUUGGCACUCUCCCUAGCGCAGACCAAGGCCAGUGUCAGCAGUCUGCAGGAGGUAGCCAUGUUCCUACAAGCCUCUGUCCUGGAGCGGGACUCAGAACAGCAAAGGCUGCAGGAUGAACUGGAGCUCACCAGACGGGCUCUGGAGAAGGAGCGGCUACACAGCCCAGGUGCAACCAGCACAGCAGAACUGGGGUCCAGAGGGGAGCAGGGUGUGCAGCUGGGAGAGGUCUCAGGAGUGGAGGCUGAGCCUAGUCCUGAUGGAAUGGAGAAGCAGUCAUGGAGACAAAGGCUUGAACACCUGCAGCAAGCAGUGGCCCGGCUGGAGAUUGACAGGAGCAGGCUGCAGCGCCACAAUGUCCAGCUGCGGAGUACCUUGGAGCAGGUGGAGCGAGAACGGAGGAAGCUGAAGAGGGAGGCCAUGCGUGCGGCCCAGGCAGGGUCCCUAGAGAUCAGCAAGGCCACGGCUUCUUCACCCACACAGCAGGAUGGGAGAGGACAGAAGAACUCAGAUGCCAAGUGUGUGGCUGAACUGCAGAAAGAGGUGGUCCUGCUGCAAGCUCAGCUGACUUUGGAGCGGAAGCAGAAGCAGGACUACAUCACCCGCUCAGCACAGACCAGCCGUGAGCUAGCAGGCCUGCACCACAGCCUCUCACACUCACUUCUUGCCGUGGCCCAGGCCCCUGAGGCCACUGUCCUGGAGGCAGAGACCCGCAGGCUGGAUGAGUCCCUGACUCAAAGUCUGACAUCCCCAGGGCCAGUCCUGCUACACCCCAGCCCCAGCACUACCCAAGCCGCCUCCAGGUAGCAGCCACAGCCAGGAGCACACAGACAGAAGACUGUGUCAUGGGUCAUGGCCCCUCCGCACACCUACAGGUUUGCCAAAGGAAAAGCCUGGCUCUGUUAGGCACCCAGGAGCCCCAGGUCGGCGGGUGUUCCCAGGAAGAGGAAGUAAAUCUGCAACCCUGGGGAGGACCCCAACUCACCUGGGAAUGAGGCAAAUUGCAUUUGCUUGCUCCCUAUGGAAUCACCCAGAGGGGUGCCUUGCCCUGGCUGAGGGACAUGUACUGCCUCUCAUCUAGAAUUUAUUUUCCUAGCACUUCACCACCUCCUUCAUCUUCUCCUUCAACAAUAAACCCUGGGAUCUUUGCAUUCAUUUUCUGCUGCUGUCUCCACUUGUGCAGCUGGGUGGCAGCACCACAUCAAGGGAGUUUAUCUGGGAAGAACUUGCCAAAGAUUCCUGUUGAGGUAGCAUGCAUUUAUUGUACACCAUGCACUGUGAUAGGGAAGGGUUACAGAGAACACACAAGACAAAGCCCCUGUCCACAGACAGCCUACAGUCCAGUUGAUGAGAACAGGCUAACACUCAUUUAUGAGUCAGAGGCAAUUCUGUGUACUGACUAGAAGAACUGUAGAAAUUCCAGGGGCUGAGGAAGGGAGGCACGAACUGGCCCUUGAAAGAUGGAGUGGGGUUGGAGGUGUUGCCAAGCACACAGUGAGAAGACUGGUCUGACUGUGGCAGGGGGUUGGGGCUGAGCUUGGGUGGGUUGAGCGGGGAGAUUUUGGAGGGUUAAAAGAAGUUCUGGGGCCUCAAAAACACAGCGUUGACCUUUAGCUAAAGUCAGAGUCUCUGAGUUCAGAAGCUCCACAUGGCCUCAUUCCUCUUCUACUCUGGGUGAAUGUCCUUGAGAUGUCGCUUCCUGGGCAUAUCAGCUGGAACUGAUCUGGUCGCCUGUAGUCCAACCAUGUGUCAAGCCAAUCAGAAGGAUGGACUAUGGCGGAACUUCUCACCCAUGGACUGGUCCUAGUGGAGGCUGGACAGAACCCAGCUCACAGGCUUAAGACCUAUUGCUGGCAACCUCCUCAAAGCCUAAAAAUUGUUUAAUUUUUUUAAGAGACAGGGUUUUGUCCUGUCUUCCAAGCUGGAGUGCAGUGGCACAAUCACAUCUUACUGCAGCCUGAAACUCCUGGGCUCAAGUGAUCCUCCCACCUCAACCUCUCAAAGUGCUGGGAUUACCGGUGUGAGCCACCAUGCCCAACCAGAACAGUUUUCCUUAAAGAAGCAGGCCAUUACCUUCCUCUGGCACUCCCACCAUAAUCUGGAAUUCCUCUUUACUAAGCCUGGGGAUGGAACUGAGACCUAGCCAAGAAUCUGGGAGGGGUAAGAGCAGCACCCACUCACCCAGACCUCCUAAUUUGGGGCUCAGCCCCAUUAUGUCUCAUUGCACCACACAGAGUGGAAAUGGGGCUGUUCACAGCGACUAGAGCUUUGUUCCAGAAACCUACACAUGCAGCUCAGCAACAGAUGCUUAGUGAAAACUUCUGAAACCCCAGAAACAGAUCUGGGGCCCCAGAAAUGCUGUCCUGGUCCCUAUUUCCAGUCAGAUUCCCUGUAGCUUAAAAUCCUUACCUGGCUUUUAGGCCAUUUAUUUCUUUUUCCUUUUUUUUUUUUUGAGACAGAGUUUUGCUCUUGUUGCCCAGGCUGGAGUGCAGUGACGUAAUCUCGGCUCACCAGUGGCAACAUCCACCUCCUGGGUUCAAGCAAUUCUCCUGCCUCGGCCUCCUGUGUAUCUGGGAUUAUAGACACGUGCCACCAUGCCCGGCUAAUUUUGUAUUUUUAGUAGAGACAGGGUUUCUCCAUGUUGAUCAGGCUGGUCUCGAACUCCCGACCUCAGGUGAUCCACCCACCUCGGCCUCCCAAAAUGUUGGGAUUACGGGCAUGAGCCACCGCGCCCGGCCCUUUAGGCCAUUUUUAUGCUAGGAGUUGUCAGAGACAAGACUUCUCUUGGUUGUUCACUUGUUACAUCCUCCAGCCCUGGUUCUCAGGCUCGGGCUGACAGAGGGUCCCUGUUUUUUACCUUAGAGUUUCUUCUCAGCAUCAUUUUCUGUAGGUCAUGAGCCAGGGCCUUAGGCCCCACAUACCUUCUGGGCCUCAGAGAGGUUCCAGCAGCUGAAAGACAUCUUAGAGGCUGCCAAGCAGGGUCUUUAUUCAGGACUAGACUAAUCUGUAUUUGCUCUUCUCUUUCCAUCCAACCCUCAAGAGCCCCCCAGCUCCAUUAUAGACCUCGGCCUAGGGUCUCCCCUCCCCACCAGAUAUUCAGAGCAGGGCUGGCCUUCAGUUCAAGUGUAGACUGUGCUCUUGCCCUCACACUCGAGCUUGUGGAUGAUCUUCCACUCCGGCUUUCUAAAGUACACUUUCCUUGCCCAGUAGCAGGAUUGCCUCUGUGGAGUGUCCCACCAAUAAUGGUGACAACUGCUGUUUUCAUCAGCUCCAGACCCAAAGAGACCUGAAGUGGGGAAGUGUGAAGGAAGGAAUAUGUGUCAUCCAGGGGGGACCCAACUUUGCCUAAGGGCAUGAGGCCGGAGCCUCCUUUCCUGACCUUGUCACAUGUGGCAGGGUAUAACCAGAAUGGUGAAUCCAGCAGACGGGAGGAGUCCCUGGCAGUCCAGCCAGUUCUCGUGGAUGUACUUGAGGAAGGUGCAAUUGGCCACCAGAACAUGCAGGAGUAGAGGUUAGAGCUCAGCCACAGAGAUUAUCUUCUUGCAGAAAACUUUUUUCCCCCUUCCUAAUCUUGUCUGCUUUGAUAGAAGCUGGUACUGGCUGGAAAGGCCUGAAAGCAGGAGGGGACAAGAGUCGUCAGAGGCUGGGCAAUGUUCUUGUUUCCGGGGAGUGCUGAGGUCCGGCGGGUGCUGCCCCUGUUCUCUCAAGGAUCCCACGUGCUUUGUGUGUUAGAGCAGUGACCAUCACCUCCCAACCCAAGGACCUUUGCUGCUCUGCUUCCCACAUGGGACUGCCAGCACCCUGAAGGCAGAAAAACUGAAUGUACCCGUUAAAGGAGGAGAAGCUGGUGGUGUAUGUUGAGAUAAGGAGGGUGGGGAGUGUACAGUUACAGGCUGCACAGGGAGGGCAAGAUCAAUGUUGACACCAAAGUGCCAAAGGCUGUCUGCGCCAGGUCUGGGGCCCCCACUGGUCAUACCGCCUGAUAAAACCAUUGCAGUCCACACUAGGUCUGGAGGCUUCGACACCCACAGCAUGUGGGUGUUCUCAUGCAGGCCAUGAGUAUUCGGGGUGCUUUAAGUGCAGGGGAGUUCUGUUGUCCACGUUAUUCUUAAAGCCCAGAAUAGGCCCUGUUUUAUUCUACAGAGAUAGGAAGGCACUGGGGCUCACAGAGUGGUGCUGCUUCCCACCCUCACCCUUCUGCCCCCACCUGAGCACAGUGUGGUGCUCAGUGAUGGUUAUCCUAUAUUCCAAAUACGCAUGGCCCAGGACUGGCAGAGUCGGAGCUCGGGGUCUAGCUGUGACCUGGGGAUCGGUUGGAGUAGCUUCUUGACCAGCCGGAAUUGGGUUAGGUGUCCUAGCAUUGGUGCCUAUGGAGAAGAACACAGACUGUUUAUCACUCACCCCUGGUUCCAGUACCAAGGAAAGGCUGGAGCCAUUGCAACUGGAGGCCCAGCGGAGGAAGGGAUCAAGAAGAGGAUGCAGCCCAGAGCCCAGGACCGAGCAUCCACCGGCCUCUGGAGAUGGCGUGGUCUCCAGUUGCAUCGGGGCUUCAGGGCCCAUCUGAAGUGCUGAUCAAACCAGGCAGACACACCAUGCUGGUGAAGGCAGGCUUUGUAGAUGCGGGGCUGAAUUGAGCAGCCACAGAACCUCUGCAGCUCUGGGGCCAGUGGCAGAACUUCUAGAAGUACCUGUGGGGUGGGAAACCCCAGCCACAAAAGCAGUGAGCUGACUUCCAGGCCUGAGGCUUUGCCUGCAGGCCUCAUCUCAGCCCAUGGGACAGAUUCCUGGUUUUUUUAGUUUGGCCUUGGGGUAGAUGAUACCUUCAGCUGUCCACCCUGCAAUACCUCACCUCCUGCCUUCUGACCCAGUACUCUGCAGAGCGGGGGAAUGGGGCCAGGGGACAGGGGCAGGGAAGAGGAAGAAGCAAGAGCUGCCAGUGUGCUCCAAACCAAGAGAGCCCUCCACAUGAUUCUGGGCACAGCUGAGGAGGAGUGCAAGCUCAACUCUGCUCACCACACUUAAGAAGCAGGCAAGGGAGGAUGAAGGGCAAAAACAUGGGGUCCUGAGGCCCUUUUACUCCCUCUACCCUGCUGGAGGUGAGGAUGAGAGGUGAGACUUCGUUGGACUGUGCUCCUGGCCAGUUGAUCUCACCCAACUCAUUACAUCAGUAGCCUGGUCACAGGGUGGACACUCUGACCUCUUCUUAGCCUUUCAUUGGCAAUACUACCAGCUCUAUAUAUGCCCUUAUAGGGCCUGAACCUUGGCUCAGGUGGAUGGGCUUGGAGGUAAAAUAAUUGAAUGGGUCAGGGGUAGGAGGAGAGAUGAGUCUCUGCCAAGGCUGUGUGAUGUGUCAUCUGAGAGAGUGGGUAACCCCUAUUCCCAGCACAUGGCCAUUUAUUUAGAGCCAGGGAGGGGGACGAGAAUUCAUAUUCAAAUGUGAUUCUUUCUUAAUUACUACCAGUUGUUCAGGUGAGGGAAUCAGGGAAGGCCAGAUUAAUAAUCCACACAUUGCCCUUGCACCUCCUGUCUUGGUUUCCUAUCAAAACCUCUCCCGUAUCUAUGAACAUUCCAGCCCUGCAGGUCAGAUUGCUGGCCAGGAGUAGUCUCACAUUCUAGCUGACUGAUGGCCUCGGCUUCUGCUGUUGUAUGUGGUUUGAUGAUUCAUGCUGGAGCCUUUGGCUAUAACUCUCUUCCCUGUAUAAGGGCCAUCUGAAGUUUGUCUGCCUGACUCCAUUACCUGGUGAAUGAGAUUGGCUAGCUGCUGCUCCUGCCCCAGCUAUUCAGUCAUUUGGCAAAUACUCAUUUAAACAAAGCUCCACAGGGAUCUCUGAGAAGGAGCUCACCUCUAGGCACACAGAACCUGGACACAGAUGAAAGUUUGCAGAAUGACCCAGUUGUGCAGAAGAGACCCACUGGCUGCUCUCAGUGAGGCCAGGGAGAGUCAAACAGAGCAUCUUGGACAAAGAGAGGGCUUGAAGGCCCUUUCAAAGUGUCAAGCCAGUUGGAUGCACGGGUUGUGUGGAGUCCAGGGGUACAUCCAGAAGCAAUGGCAGGUGUUAUCCAUUCAUUCAGGUUAGACCUCUGAGCAGACGGCAGAAACGUCAGCCACAGGUGAGCAUAAGCUCAAACCCCCCCAUUGAAGGCUACAUUCUUGUCCCACAGGGCAGAGCACAUGGCAAGUGGCAUGCUGACUCAGACACCGGGCACUGAGAAAAGUGGGAAGCCAUGGUCACAGACUCUACAUUCCCCUCUCCUGUUGGCCUCCAUCCCUUCCUCAACCGUCCGCAGAACACCUCCUUCCAGCACCUUAGCUCCUGCCUCCCUCUGGACCUAUUCAGUCCUCAAGGGUGCCCUGCUAAAGGCUGGGCUGAAAGCUAAGAGGAGAGGUGGCAUUCAAUGUGUCCUGUGUCCUCCCUGGGGUUGAUUAAGGGGUCGAUGCCCAAUAGAGUCCUUCAUCUUGGUGUUCAGCCCAGGGUCCAGCUGCCAAGGGAAGGCUUGGCAAUCAAGGGUGAUGGAGAUAAGAAUGAAAAGGGGCACCACCCUGUGCCAAAGCUGGCAUGUUGUAUAUCUGAGAGAGGAGCUGCCUAUUCACAGUGUAGGGUUGUCAAGCUGGAGGCAGGGAGAGAAAAGCAAGAGCUUUUUGGUUCCUCUUGAGGAUAGAAUCUAUAGGAAAAUGUAAGAGGGUUAAAAAUAAAUUUCCCAUGCAUCCAAACUUUUUUCUUUGGUAGACUUUCUUGUCAUCUAUUUAAAAUGAAACAAGUGCAUGUACGUGGUUAAGACAUUUUAGCUAGGAAUGAUGGUGCGUGCCUGUAGUCCCAGCUACUUGGGAGGCUGAGGCAGGAGGAUCGCUUGAACCUGGAAGGUCAAGGCUGCAGUGAGCCGAGAUCAUACCACUGCACUCCAGCCUGAGUGAUAAAAGUGAGACCCUGUCUCAAAAAAAAAAAAAAAAUUAAAGAAGUUAAACAGUGCCGGGCUUGGGGGCUCACGCCUGUAAUCCCAGCACUUUGGGAGGCCCAGGCAGGCAGAUUGCUUGGGCUCAGGAAUUCAAGACCAUCCUAAGCGAAAAAAUAUAAAAAUUAGCUCAGUGUGAUGAUGUGCCUGUAGUCCCAGCUACUCGGGAGGCUGAGGUGGGAGGAUCACCUGAGCCCAGGGAGGUCAAGGUUGCAGUGAACCAUGAUCAUGUCACUGCACUCACUCCAGCCUGGGCAACAGAGCAAGACUGUCUCAAAAAAAAAAAAAAAGGAAAUUAAAUAAAAAGAAGAUAGCAGUUUCCCACCUCAUUCUUCUCAAACUCCUCUUCAGAGGCAGCGGGUUUUGUUUUUUUUUUAACUAUGUUUUUCUACUGGCUCACUUUAUUCCUCUAAAAUAGUAACUUGUCUAUGUGGUGCCAUAACGGGUCCAGUAUCUGGACACGAGGCCGCACUACCUACACCUUUGGGGAUUCUCGGAUCCUGACUCUGAGCUACCUCAUUCCUAGACACCUGGUGCACCACAAUGUGUCAGGGAUGUCGGUUUAUGUGGGAUAUUUGCAUUUUGUUAGGUUGUGUGUGGUAGUUGAGCAGCCAAGGGGGUAGCAUGCGGUGGAUAUUUGUUUUAGAUACACAGUAACUGGAAACUCAUUUACUGAGGCUAUUUGGUUACCCUGAACUACUGUUUCUACCAAAAAGGCAGGAUAAAUGCUCCCUCAACACACACCUUUAAUUACCAAUUUUCAGAGUAAGGGGUUGAGGUAAUAGCCACCGCCAGUUUUCCCUUUCUCUUUGAGUAUCAUUAUGAGCUCAAAGUUUUUUAUAUAUUCACUAUGAUUCAAUCAUGACAGUUGCUAUUUUUGAUGCUCAAAUUGCCGCAAAUCUAAUGUCCAAGUGUUCUUGUACUUGUCUAGGCCUAGAAUCUUUUAGUGAAGAAAAAGUAUUUAGAAGACAAAAAUCAGGCUGAGUGCAGUGGCUCACGCCUGUAAUCCUAGCACUUGUGGGAGGCUGAGGCAGGCGGAUUGCCUGAGCUCAGGAGUUGGAGACCAGCCUGGGCAACAUGGUGAAACCCCGUCUCUACUAAAAUACAAAAAAUUAGCCGGGGGUGGCGGUGUGCACCUUGUAGUCCCAGCUACUCAGGAGGCUGAGGCAGGAGAAUUGCUUGAACCCAGGAGGCAGAGGUUGCAGUGAGCUGAGAUCGCGUCACUGCACUCCAGCCUGGGUGGCAGAGCAAGACUCCGUCUCAAAAAAAAAAAAAAUACGAAAAACAAAAAACAUAAUCUGGAUUGCAGGGCUGAUCGUUGCUAAUGGAGUGUUAUGGCUGUUCAGAUGACAGAGGGAGAAAAUGUACUUUGUAAACUGUUAGUUCAAUGAGGUUAUGAUUGCACAACAAUGUGAACAUACUUAAUGCCACUGAACUUUAUUGCCAUUGAUAACUUUUAAAUGGUAAAUUUUGUGUAUUAUUUUGUCACAAUAAAAAGUUUGAAAAUCGA